GGCUGGAAAAUCACAGCUGAUGACAGGGCGAGUAGCUGGUGGGAUCGAGAAGCGGGGGGUCUUGGGCAGCCCCACCCCGAAAAAAGGGCUCAGCCUGCGGGUUCAGGGGGUGGGUCGCAGAUAUCCGGUAGGAGCUCGGCCCCAGGAGGACAAAGUUCUGGGGCGAGCCCUCUUUCCUGGGCCCUUGGAGACAGUGUGGGUGCGUUCGCGUCCAGUCCGCAGAGCCAUGGUUCCUGGACAGCGAUUUCCGGUGCUGUCCAGAGUGCUGACAGAGCGGACCCCGGCUGGGGGUAGCCAUGGGGGACAGAGGUUCGAUGCGGGCCCCAUGCCUCUCCUCAGUGCCCGGCUCAGAGCCGACUCGAGGCGGGCGGACUCCAGGAUGAUCCACUCUGUCUGUCUGUUGCUUUUCUCUAGGAACCUGCUAGACCUUGAUACCUUCUCCAAGUCCGACCCCAUGGUGGUGCUUUACACGCAGAGCCGGGCCAGCCAGGAGUGGCGGGAGUUCGGACGGACCGAGGUGAUUGAUAACACGCUGAACCCAGACUUCGUGCGCAAAUUCGUCCUCGACUAUUUCUUUGAGGAAAAGCAAAAUCUGCGCUUCGAUGUGUACAACGUGGACUCCAAAACCAACAUCUCCAAACCGAAGGAUUUCCUGGGACAAGCGUUCCUGGCCCUGGGAGAGGUGAUUGGAGGCCAGGGCAGCCGAGUAGAGCGAACCCUCACGGGUGUACCAGGCAAGAAGUGUGGGACCAUAUUGCUGACUGCAGAAGAGCUUAGCAAUUGUCGGGACAUUGCCACCAUGCAGCUGUGUGCAAACAAGCUGGACAAGAAGGACUUCUUUGGGAAAUCAGACCCCUUCCUUGUGUUCUACAGGAGCAAUGAGGAUGGCACGUUCACCAUCUGCCACAAGACAGAGGUUGUGAAAAACACGCUGAAUCCUGUGUGGCAGCCCUUCAGCAUCCCUGUGCGGGCUCUGUGCAAUGGAGACUAUGACAGAACGGUGAAGAUUGAUGUGUACGACUGGGACCGGGAUGGAAGCCACGAUUUCAUUGGUGAGUUCACCACCAGCUACCGGGAGCUGAGCAAGGCCCAGAACCAGUUCACAGUAUAUGAGGUUCUUAACCCUCGGAAGAAAUGUAAGAAGAAGAAAUAUGUCAACUCAGGAACUGUGACGCUGCUCUCCUUCUCUGUGGACUCUGAAUUCACUUUUGUUGAUUACAUCAAGGGAGGGACACAGCUGAACUUCACAGUAGCCAUUGACUUCACGGCUUCCAAUGGGAAUCCUCUGCAGCCUACCUCCCUGCACUACAUGAGUCCCUACCAGCUCAGCGCCUAUGCCAUGGCCCUCAAGGCAGUGGGAGAGAUCAUCCAGGACUAUGACAGUGAUAAGCUCUUCCCAGCUUAUGGCUUUGGGGCCAAGCUGCCCCCAGAGGGACGGAUCUCCCACCAGUUCCCCCUGAACAACAAUGAUGAGGACCCCAACUGUGCGGGCAUCGAGGGUGUGCUGGAGAGCUAUUUCCAGAGCCUGCGCACAGUGCAGCUCUAUGGGCCCACCUACUUUGCUCCUGUCAUCAACCAAGUGGCCAGGGCUGCAGCCAAGAUCUCUGAUGGCUCCCAGUACUAUGUUCUGCUCAUCAUCACUGAUGGGGUCAUCUCUGACAUGACGCAGACCAAGGAGGCCAUCGUCAGCGCCUCCUCAUUGCCCAUGUCUAUCAUUAUCGUCGGUGUAGGACCAGCCAUGUUUGAGGCAAUGGAAGAGUUGGACGGUGAUGAUGUGCGCGUGUCCUCUAGGGGACGCUACGCAGAGCGGGACAUCGUUCAGUUCGUCCCAUUCCGAGACUAUGUUGACCGGUCGGGGAACCAGGUGUUGAGCAUGGCCCGACUGGCCAAGGAUGUGCUGGCCGAGAUCCCGGAGCAGCUGCUGUCCUAUAUGCGCACCAGAGACAUCCAGCCUCGGCCCCCACCCCCUGCCAACCCCAGCCCGAUCCCAGCUCCAGAGCAGCCCUGAGGAUUCCACAUAUCCAAUGCCUCACAGUCUGCAAGCCUGCUCACCCACUGCUUCUGCUUUAAGCCAGAGGCACCUGGAACCCUGGACUUCACUGGGAGGGCCAACUUGGAGGAUCAGUGCUGGCUGACAAGCCCUCCGCCUCCUUGCCUGCAGAGGGCCUGGCACUAUCACCACCUCUCUGCCUUCAUGCCAAUAAUAAAGCUGAUCUUUAUUCCA